GCAAUGCGAACGUGGGCUUUUCAAGCGGUGUCAAGCCCAGGGCUCUUUCUCUGCACCGCCCUGCCACUCCGGCAAUGAGGCGGAAUUUUGAGAGCUGGAAAAAGAAUUCUGCGUUAGUCCACCCCGCUGAUUUUACAGAUGUUCGGAGCCUUACGGCAUAGGAGGCCGUGAUUCUGUGUCAGGGAGACAGGGACAGAUGGCUUCCGAAGCAAGGGUUAGACCUGUUCAGCUGGAGAUGCAGCUUUGGUCAUGGUGGAGUUUUGCAGAAACCCGCGGACACCCGCGUUCCUGCUGCAGGCACAGAUGUCCACCGGGCAUCUGUGUCUCAAAGGGUGGUGAUGCUGUCACUUUAGUAAAGGAAUAUUGAGGUUACCAAACAGGCCGGGGCCUGAUGCAGAUGAGGAGUAUAGACUUAAAUUUUAAGUGCAAAAACAACUUUAAAUGCAGUCUCAUUAUUACUGCCUGUCUCAUUUGUACUGUAAUGAAGGGUGAAUAUUUUUGGCACUCACUUAUUCUGGAAUAUGGGUAACUUGCCUUUAGGUCUGUUUUAUAGUAAUUCUUUUACACAAACAUGAAGAUCUUGUAUUAAAACACUUUCAUAACUAAUGAUGCUGUAGUAUGUGGCAGGCGAGUGGUAACGCUAAUAUUUAGGGUUUGAGCAUAGUCUAGCUCUGCUUGUUUACAUAGCUGAGUUAAACGGAUGAGCAGGACUGAUUAAUCUGUAGUAGUUUUUGCAAGACUGAAGUACCUGACAGCAUUCGGGGAUCAUUUCUCAGUUGGUGUUCCGUUUAUUACUUUCACAGCAUGAAUACCGACACGGUGAUCAGCAAGUUAGUUUAUCCUCUACCCAUUUUUCUCUAAAAUAUUGAAUUAAAGGAUCUCUAAGGUCCUCUUCUGUCUCGAGUUCUCCGAUUUUACAUGUUAACUUGAAACACGUCACUCAUUGUGAUAAUAAAAAUGUUUUAAGAAGAAAAGAUUUUUAGAAUUCUGCAUAAUGGGGCAUAGCGAAUCUUCAAAUUCAUUAUUCUCAGCUCUCUCAGUCACUUUAUCAGGGUUGGGCUAAAAUAAGUGAAAAGUGACUUUUCAAAUUGCAGAUACUUACGUGUUAAAUUCACUUAAAUUCAGAGGCUGCAAUGGAGUGAUUUCUGGAGGGUGGAGAGUAGCUCAAGUCUGGCUUGGGAACGGGGUUCGUGCAGUGCACUGAUAACUUUUGCAAUAAGCCAAGAACAGUCUGACUCAGAGAAUGUGAUAAAUUGACUUUUAUACAGUGUUCAUAUUGUGUAUUUUUUGGCUGAGAUAAUAAUAAUCUUCAUAAACGAUCUGUUUAAAUAUGCACCAGUUAUUUAUUUGUCUUGCAGCCCCAAGGCAGGGCAUUUCCCUCAACGUUCCAUCAAUCUCUUCCUCUUUUCUGGCUCCUGACUUCAGGUGAUCCGCCUGCCUCAGCCUCCCAAAAUGCUGGGAUUACAGGCGUGAGCCACCGAGCCUGGCUUUUGGCUUAUUUUCUAGGUUUAGUAUUCUGUUGUUUCUAGAGUCAGCUAAUGGAUUACCUACAACAUGGUAUUAUUACGAGAUUAUCUCCUGUGAAAUUCUCGAAUGUGCUUGAUCAUCUGCCAAAGCAUCCUUAGAAUUCAUUCAGAAUACUUCUGGAAAGUUUUGCAACACCAAUUCAAUUAAUAUGAAAUAGUUUCUUAUUAUACACACUCUGGAAAACAUCUGAAUAAGCUAAUUUUCAAGAUUGGUUAACUUAGUCUUGUUGGUCAGGAGUUAAUUAUGAGUUAUUAGUUUCUUGCCUGGAAAGGCAGAAAGUUCUUAAGUAGCAGCAGUAAAAUGAGCUCUUUAAUGAAAGAGCCGUUAAACCAAGAUGUUAACUUUUAGUUGUGUUCUUUAUCCUCCCUGCUAUGAAAGGCAGCUGUGGGAGGUGAAAUAGAGUAGCUAAAAUGUAUUAUUUCAUUUUUAGAUUUCUAGAUCUUUUCUUCUGACUGAAGGACGUGACCACCAAGAAUUGAACCAGCACUUGAGGGCAGGCACAUAGGGCAUUGUGUGAGGAGUCUGAAGGCAUGGCUUUUGGUCCUUACUUGUUUAUUCACUGAACACAUUCUCACUGAGCACCUGUGUGUGCUGAGAGGGUGGGCACCUGUGUGUGCCGGGAGGAGGAACACCUGUAUGUGCUUGUGGGGGGCACCUGUGUGUGCCGGGGUCGUGGUAGCACUUGUGUAUGCUGUGGGUGCUGGGAGGGGGAACCAGUUUGAACAAAACAGACUAAGCCCUCGUGGAACAGACACAUUCUAAUUGGGUGGAAACAGACAAAUAUGUGAAUGAAUAGGUCAAAGGAUCAUAAUGCUGUGGAGAACUUUAGAGUCAGGAAAGGGUAAGAGUGUGUGUGUGUGUAUGUAUAUGUGUGGUAGGGGAUUUACUUUUUAUAUAGAGGGGUCAAAUAAAGCCUCUACUGAGAUAACUUUUUUUUUUUUGGAGACAGAGUCUUGCUCUGUCACCCAGGCUGGAGUGCAGUGGCGUGAUCACAGCUCACUGUAGCCUCAACCUCCUGGGCUCAAGUGAUCCUCCCAUCUCAGCCUCCCGAGUAAGCUGGGACUGCAGGCUUAUAUCACCACGCUGGGCCAAUGUUUGUAUUUUUAGUAGACGCGGGGUUUCACUAUGUCGCUCAGGCUGGUCUGGAACUCCUGGCCUCAAGCGAUCCACCCACCUUGGCCUCCCAAAGUGCUGGGAUUACAGGCAUGGGCCACCACACCUGGCCUAACUCAUGGUGGGAGACUGGAAGGAAAUGAGGAAGUGAGCAGGAGGCAGUGGGAUGAGCAUGUUCCAAACCCUGGUGCAGGAGCAUGCUUGGCAUGUUAGGGGUGGCAAGGUCAUGGUGGCCAGUCAGUGUGGAUGUGGGUUGGGGGGAGGUGGCAGCAGAUGAGAGGGGGUGGGAGUGGGGAGGACACAUCAGUGUAGGUCAUUGUAAGGAUUUUGGCCUUUACACUGAGUGAGGGGGAAGCCGUUGGAGAGCUUUGAACAGUGAAGUUGAUGAUGACUUAUGUUUUAAAAGGAUAACUGGCUGCUGGGUUGAGAAUAGACAGGAAGAGGACAAGGGCUGAGUCAGGGAGACCUUUUCAAGCUAGAGCUGUGUGACUCACACCAUAAUUCUUCCCUGAGUCUUCGUUUCCUCAUCUGUAAAAUAACUGGGCCCUCUCUAGCUCAAGAAUUUUAAGUUUUCAAGUAGUGCAGGGUAUUAUUUCUACAGGGAGGCAAGAGGAUUGCGUGGGAAGAGGUUCUGAAAGUAAAUCGCUUCAGAUGACCUGAAAACUUGACACCAACCUGCCUGUAGCUGAAUCAUCCCAAAUCAAGAGCAUUGGCCAGGACUACUAGAACUGUGUCAAAACAGCUGCUACACUAACGGGCAUCUUUGUCUUGUUCUCAGUCUUAAAAAGAGUUAUAAAACAUGGAGGCUGGCUCAGUGGUUCGAGCCAUUUUUGACUUCUGCCCUAGCGUAUCAGAAGAACUGCCGCUCUUUGUGGGAGAUAUUAUUGAGGUGCUGGCAGUGGUGGAUGAAUUUUGGCUUCUAGGAAAGAAGGAGGAUGUUACAGGACAAUUCCCCAGCAGUUUUGUGGAAAUUGUGACCAUUCCCAGUCUAAAAGAGGGAGAGAGGCUGUUUGUGUGCAUUUGUGAAUUCACAUCCCAAGAGUUGGAUAAUCUUCCCCUCCAUCGAGGUGACCUGGUGAUUCUCGAUGGCAUUCCCACUGCAGGCUGGCUGCAGGGCCGAAGCUGCUGGGGCGCACGGGGCUUCUUCCCAUCUUCAUGUGUCCGCGAGCUCUGCCUCUCCUCACAGAGCCGGCAGUGGCACUCCCAGAGCGCCCUGUUUCAGAUUCCGGAAUAUUCCAUGGGACAAGCCCGGGCCCUAAUGGGGCUUUCUGCUCAGCUGGAUGAAGAGCUGGACUUCAGGGAAGGGGAUGUGAUCACCAUUAUUGGAGUUCCUGAACCAGGCUGGUUUGAAGGGGAGUUAGAGGGCCGAAGAGGCAUUUUUCCAGAAGGUUUUGUAGAGCUGUUGGGGCCCCUGAGGACUGUGGAUGAGUCAGUAAGUUCUGGAAAUCAAGAUGACUGCAUUGUUAAUGGUGAAGUAGAUACCCCUGUAGGAGAAGAAGAGAUAGGGCCGGAUGAGGAUGAGGAGGAGCCAGGGACCUAUGGGGUCGCCCUGUACAGAUUCCAAGCCCUGGAGCCAAAUGAGCUGGAUUUCGAGGUCGGGGAUAAAAUCCGAAUUCUGGCGACCUUGGAAGAUGGCUGGCUGGAAGGAUCCCUGAAGGGCAGGACAGGCAUCUUUCCUUACCGGUUUGUGAAAUUAUGUCCUGACACACGGGUGGAGGAAACCAUGGCUCUGCCCCAGGAAGGCAGCCUUGCCAGGAUCCCGGAAACUUCUUUGGAUUGUUUGGAGAACACCUUAGGAGUAGAGGAACAAAGACAUGAAACCAGUGACCAUGAGGCCGAGGAGCCUGACUGCAUUAUUUCUGAAGCACCCACUUCUCCCCUCGGUCAUCUGACUUCAGAGUAUGACACAGACAGAAACUCUUAUCAGGACGAGGACACCGCAGGAGGGCCCCCGAGAAGCCCAGGCGUGGAGUGGGAAAUGCCUCUUGCCACAGACUCUCCCACAUCUGACCCUACAGAAGUAGUCAAUGGUAUUUCCUCCCAACCUCAGGUCCCUUUUCAUCCCAACUUGCAGAAAAGCCAGUAUUAUUCUACAGUGGGAGGGAGCCACCCGCACUCAGAACAGUACCCCGACCUUCUUCCCCUAGAAGCAAGGACUAGAGACUAUGCCAGCCUACCUCCCAAAAGAAUGUAUUCCCAGCUAAAAACUCUUCAGAAGCCAGUGCUCCCUCUUUACAGGGGCUCUUCUGUUUCAGCUUCAAGGGUAGUCAAACCCAGACAAUCAAGUCCUCAGCUCCACAACCUAGCAAGUUAUACUAAAAAGCACCACACGUCCAGUGUUUACUCCAUCUCAGAGAGAUUGGAGAUGAAGCCUGGUCCGCAAGCCCAAGGGCUUGUUAUGGAAGCAGCAACACAUUCACAGGGAGACGGCAGCACUGACCUGGACUCGAAGCUGACACAACAGCUGAUCGAGUUUGAGAAGAGCUUGGCAGGGCCCGGCACAGAGCCAGAUAAAAUUUUACGCCACUUUUCAAUCAUGGACUUUAACUCUGAGAAGGAUAUUGUCCGAGGUUCCUCAAAGUUAAUCACCGAGCAGGAGCUGCCGGAAAGGAGAAAGGCCCUAAGGCCACCGCCACCUCGUCCCUGUACUCCGGUAUCCACUUCUCCCCAUUUGCUGGUUGACCAGAACCUAAAACCUGCACCACCCUUGGUGGUGCGACCCUCUCGCCCAGCUCCCCUGCCUCCCUCAGCACAGCAGAGAACGAAUGCGGUAUCCCCCAAGCUCCUAUCUCGACACCGUCCUACCUGUGAGACCUUAGAAAAGGAGGGCCCUGGUCAUAUGGGAAGGAGUCUGGACCAGACCUCCCCAUGCCCCUUAGUGCUGGUGAGGAUUGAGGAAAUGGAGCGGGACUUGGAUAUGUACAGUAGAGCUCAAGAAGAGCUAAACCUCAUGCUGGAGGAGAAGCAGGAUGAAUCAUCAAGAGCAGAGACCCUCGAGGAUCUCAAGUUCUGUGAAAGUAACAUUGAAAGUUUGAAUAUGGAACUCCAGCAACUAAGAGAAAUGACGCUCCUCUCCUCCCAGUCUUCAUCACUGGUGGCCCCUUCUGGGUCUGUGUCUGCCGAAAAUCCAGAGCAGAGGAUGCUGGAGAAGAGAGCCAAGGUCAUAGAAGAACUUCUUCAGACAGAAAGAGACUACAUUCGGGAUCUGGAAAUGUGUAUUGAGCGGAUCAUGGUACCCAUGCAGCAGGCACAGGUACCAAACAUUGAUUUUGAGGGACUUUUUGGAAAUAUGCAGAUGGUGAUUAAGGUCUCGAAGCAAUUAUUGGCUGCUCUGGAAAUCAGCGAUGCUGUAGGACCUGUGUUUCUUGGUCACCGGGAUGAGCUUGAGGGAACAUACAAGAUUUACUGCCAGAAUCAUGAUGAGGCCAUUGCGCUGCUUGAAAUCUACGAGAAGGAUGAGAAGAUCCAGAAGCAUCUUCAGGACUCCUUGGCAGAUCUGAAGAGCCUAUACAACGAAUGGGGAUGCACAAAUUAUAUUAACCUGGGCUCCUUCCUCAUCAAACCAGUACAGAGAGUAAUGCGUUACCCGCUGUUGCUAAUGGAGUUGCUGAAUUCCACCCCAGAAUCCCACCCAGAUAAAGUGCCUUUAACCAAUGCAGUCCUUGCGGUCAAGGAAAUCAACGUUAACAUUAAUGAAUAUAAACGGCGAAAGGACCUGGUCCUCAAGUACCGUAAGGGUGAUGAAGAUAGCCUUAUGGAGAAAAUUUCCAAACUGAACAUCCACUCCAUCAUCAAGAAAUCCAACCGAGUUAGCAGUCACCUGAAGCAUCUCACUGGCUUUGCUCCUCAGAUAAAAGAUGAAGUAUUUGAAGAAACAGAAAAAAACUUCCGAAUGCAAGAAAGAUUGAUUAAGUCUUUUAUCCGAGACCUGUCUCUCUACCUCCAGCACAUCCGGGAGUCCGCAUGUGUGAAAGUGGUGGCUGCUGUGAGCAUGUGGGAUGUGUGCAUGGAGAGAGGACACCGGGACCUGGAGCAGUUUGAGAGGGUGCAUCGCUACAUCAGUGACCAGCUCUUCACAAACUUUAAGGAGAGGACAGAGCGGCUUGUCAUCUCCCCCUUAAAUCAGUUACUGAGCAUGUUUACAGGGCCCCAUAAGCUGGUACAGAAACGCUUUGACAAGCUCCUGGACUUCUAUAACUGUACAGAACGGGCAGAAAAGCUAAAGGACAAGAAGACCCUGGAGGAGCUGCAGUCGGCCCGGAACAACUAUGAGGCCCUGAAUGCACAGCUGCUGGAUGAGCUGCCCAAGUUCCACCAGUACGCCCAGGGCCUCUUCACCAACUGUGUCCACGGCUAUGCUGAAGCCCACUGUGACUUUGUGCACCAGGCUCUGGAGCAAUUAAAGCCACUGCUUUCGUUACUCAAAGUGGCUGGCAGAGAGGGAAACCUUAUUGCCAUCUUCCACGAAGAGCACAGCAGAGUUCUGCAGCAACUCCAGGUUUUUACCUUCUUCCCGGAGUCUCUUCCAGCUACCAAGAAGCCAUUUGAGAGGAAAACCAUUGACCGCCAGUCUGCUCGAAAGCCACUCCUGGGCCUGCCAAGUUACAUGCUACAGUCAGAAGAACUCCGGGCCUCCCUCCUGGCCAGGUAUCCCCCUGAAAAACUCUUCCAGGCAGAACGGAACUUCAAUGCUGCUCAAGACUUGGAUGUCUCACUUUUGGAAGGUGACCUGGUGGGUGUGAUUAAGAAAAAAGACCCCAUGGGCAGCCAGAACCGCUGGCUGAUUGACAAUGGAGUCACCAAAGGCUUCGUGUACAGCUCUUUCCUAAAGCCCUACAAUCCUCGCCGCAGCCACUCCGAUGCCUCCGUGGGUAGCCACUCCUCCACAGAGUCUGAGCACGGCAGCUCCUCCCCCAGGUUCCCACGCCAGAACAGCGGCAGCACCCUGACCUUCAACCCCAGCAGCAUGGCUGUAUCCUUUACCUCGGGGUCUUGCCAGAAGCAGCCUCAAGAUGCAUCUCCUCCGCCAAAAGAAUGUGACCAAGGAACUCUCAGUGCAUCCCUAAAUCCGAGUAAUUCAGAGAGUAGUCCUUCCAGAUGCCCUUCAGACCCAGACUCCACCUCCCAGCCAAGGUCAGGGGACUCUGCAGAUGUAGCUAGAGAUGUAAAGCAACCCACUGCCACGCCGAGGAGCUACCGGAACUUCAGGCAUCCAGAAAUAGUUGGCUACUCCGUACCAGGACGAAAUGGGCAAAGUCAAGACCUCGUCAAAGGAUGUGCAAGAACAGCCCAGGCUCCGGAAGACAGAAGUACAGAGCCAGAUGGCAGUGAGGCAGAAGGCAACCAGGUCUAUUUUGCUGUCUACACCUUCAAGGCACGAAACCCAAAUGAGCUGAGCGUGUCAGCCAAUCAGAAACUCAAGAUCCUCGAGUUUAAAGAUGUUACAGGAAAUACAGAGUGGUGGUUAGCUGAGGUUAACGGGAAGAAGGGCUACGUUCCCUCCAAUUAUAUCCGCAAAACCGAGUACACCUGAGCCCACGUUGCCUGCCACCCAGCCUUGCUGCCUUUGCUUUCAGUCCGCCGAGGGUUCUGGCGGCCCACCGAGAGGGCGCCUGCUCCUGAGACACAGGCCCUGUCUGCGUUGCUUAACCAUGGCAUGGUGGAGCACACCACAGAUCUUGUUCUCCUCGAUUGGGUUGUAAACCUUGAUGCUCACUAGAAUCUCUAGAAUUUGAAAUGGACCCUGGGGCUUUGCAAAUGACUUAGUGACUAUGAGAAGAGAGACAAGUCUUAGAGCUGGCUUUUGGAAAGGAGAAACUUGCAGUCAGAAGCCCAGUGUCCUAUGUAUGCAGGAAGCUGUGCUCUAGCAAUAGACAGUGUUGGUAAUGGUUGUGCUGUACGGCGUUUGGGGUGGCCCCAUGUUCCAUGCUCAGCUGACCGGAUGCCAACUCAGAUGAAAAGAAUUCAUGGCUCUGGGCACCCCGUGAGGCAGUGCUUGCACAUGGCUGGGAGUUUGUCGGGAUUGAACCAAACCUAGUGCUUCAAAGCUCCUGGGACACCUCCAGUGUCCAGCACACAUUCUCAUACAUACUGCCCCUAAUUUCUAAAGUCCCUAAAGCACUACAUUCUGUAACCUUGUUUCUUUUACUCCAUUCCCAGAUUAGUUAUGCAAAAUUCAACUGCGUUCUACUUUUAGAAGUGUUUAGGGUCUUUAUUUUCUGUUGACCCUUCAUCUGAAAGAUUCUCUUCCCUUGUUAGGUACAAUCACUGCCCCCCCGCUUUUUUUUUUGAGAUGGGGUCUUGCUAUGUUGCCCAGGCUGGUCUUAAACGCCUGGGCUCAAGCAACCCUCCCGCCUCCCUGCUGAGAUUACAGGUGUAAGCCACCAUACCGCAACCUCAAUGACACCUUUCUGAUGGUCUUUACACAGUCUGUGAUGUCUGGUGGCCCCCCUGCCCUGGACUCAAUAAUUGAUAGAUUUUCCUAGAGUAACAGUAUGAGAGCUCCAGCCAUUCCAUUAAAAGUAUUAGUUCUGCUUUGAGCUGAAACCAGUUGAGCCUAAUGGAAGACUGGAUGUCUUUCUUCUUCAUCCAAGCACCCUAAUGACUGUUUAGUUACAUCCAUAGAUGCAGACAACAUAACACCUGUGACUUACUUGAAUUGGGAUAAGCCAUUCCAGAAGUAGCUUAUCCUAGACUUGGAAAUAAGAUUUUUUUCACCACUAACUUCCAUGCUUCAGAGAUGACAUUCAAAGCCAGAUUCCCAAGUGCCUGAUCAUACCUCCCAGUCUCAGGAAGAUAUUUGCUUACCCCUUAGACCAAGAAUCUUAAGAUCUUCCCCAGCUAUGAAGCCUAUCUUGGAAUGGGAAACCAUGAAAUUUGUCUUUUAAAAGAAAGGGAAGAAAUAGCCUUACAGCCCCUGUUCCUCCAAGUGCACAUUUAGCCUUAAAAUCCUGGGAGUCGGGAGACACCGUGGAGUCCUAACAUCCACAGUGUCUGCUGGUCGUGGUCAGAAGGCAGUAAUGCAAGAGUCCUUUUGUGAAGAGUGUUUCUAUGUAGAGAUGUUUAUAUUUAAGUAGUUCUUUUAUAAAUAAAAGCAUUUCUAAUGGCCUUGGA